GCCGGCGGAGAAGGAGGACCCGGGAGCCGGCGGCCCGGAGCUGGGAGCGCGGGGAAGGCGGUUGGGGUUCUGACAGCUGCGCGCGAUCCUGCUCUCUCUCAGCCGCCUGUGGACAUGCGCAAAGGGCCCUCUCCUGAGUCCAGAUGAUGCUCAUACCAAUGGCUUCAGUGAUGGCGGUGACUGAACCGAAAUGGGUCUCGGUCUGGAGCCGCUUCCUCUGGGUGACGCUGCUGAGCAUGGUGCUGGGGUCCCUGCUGGCCCUGCUGCUGCCGCUGGGGGCUGUGGAGGAGCAGUGCUUGGCUGUGCUCAAAGGCCUCUACCUGCUCAGGAGCAAACCGGACAGGGCGCAGCAUGCCGCCACCAAGUGCACCAGCCCGUCCACGGAGCUCAGCAUCACCUCCAGGGGCGCGACGCUGCUGGUGGCCAAGACCAAGGCCUCUCCAGCGGGUAAGUUGGAAGCCAGAGCUGCCCUGAACCAGGCCCUGGAGAUGAAGCGCCAGGGCAAGCGGGAAAAAGCCCAAAAGCUCUUCAUGCACGCCCUCAAGAUGGACCCGGACUUCGUGGACGCGCUCACCGAGUUUGGCAUCUUCUCGGAAGAAGACAAGGACAUCAUCCAGGCGGACUACUUGUACACCAGAGCAUUGACCAUCUCACCCUACCAUGAGAAAGCACUGGUCAACCGCGAUCGGACACUGCCUCUUGUGGAAGAGAUCGACCAGAGGUAUUUCAGCAUCAUCGACAGCAAAGUGAAGAAGGUCAUGUCCAUCCCCAAGGGGAACUCAGCUCUGCGCAGGGUCAUGGAGGAGACCUACUACCAUCACAUCUACCACACAGUGGCCAUCGAGGGCAACACCCUCACCCUCUCGGAAAUCAGGCACAUCCUGGAGACCCGCUACGCCGUGCCCGGGAAGAGCCUGGAGGAGCAGAACGAGGUCAUAGGCAUGCAUGCAGCCAUGAAGUACAUCAACACGACUCUGGUUUCGCGCAUCGGCUCCGUCACCAUCAGCGACGUGCUGGAGAUCCACAGGCGGGUGCUGGGCUACGUGGACCCCGUGGAAGCCGGCAGGUUUCGGACAACACAGGUCCUGGUCGGACACCACAUCCCUCCCCAUCCGCAGGAUGUGGAAAAGCAGAUGCAGGAGUUUGUACAGUGGCUCAACUCCGAGGAAGCCAUGAACCUGCACCCAGUGGAGUUUGCAGCCUUAGCCCAUUAUAAACUCGUUUACAUCCACCCUUUCAUUGAUGGCAACGGGAGGACCUCCCGUCUGCUCAUGAACCUCAUCCUCAUGCAGGCGGGCUACCCGCCCAUCACCAUCCGCAAGGAGCAGCGGUCCGACUACUACCACGUGUUGGAAGCUGCCAACGAGGGCGACGUGAGGCCUUUCAUUCGCUUCAUCGCCAAGUGUACUGAGACCACCCUGGACACCCUGCUUUUUGCCACAACUGAGUACUCGGUGGCACUGCCAGAAGCCCAACCCAACCACUCUGGGUUCAAGGAGACGCUUCCUGUGAAGCCCUAACCCUAGAAAUCCUCAGUGACAAAGGCUGUCCUGAGGUAGGAAAAAAAAAAAGAAACAGCAUUUCUAGAAACCUAGUCACUUCCUAAAGCAAAAGGAGAAACAUUCUUUACCUCCAAAUGUUUUAGUUUUAAAAAAAAAAAAAAACUAAGUUAUGAAGCCUUGUCUCUAAAAUAACUUAUAAUUCAACCAAGCUAUUUAUUUUCUUCUUUGGAGCAAGCUAGUCAGUAUUGUAUGGUGUCUGCUGUGUCUUGCUGGUGGCCGUGCUUUAGGGGCAACAGUGCCACCAUGUGACCAGAACAAAGGUUCUGGAGCAGAAUUUGCACUAAGGUGGAGGAGCGGCCAAGAGGUGUGGGACGGGGCCCAGAGCCACUGACAUAACUCCUCCAAGUGCUUCUCUGAAACAGGCUGAGAGGUUCUGUGACUGCAACUGGGAAGUCAGACCCAAGUCGCAGCUGAGAGAAAUGGUUGAAAGCUCACUUUCUCAAGGUUUAGAUUAGUGGUGACUAACUUCCAAGCAAACUUCAUAGAAGAGAAAAUGAAUGCCGACAUUCCUUACUUACCUGCAGGAAGACUUUUUGAGCCAUAGUUUGCAAACUUUAGUGCCAGCAGCUGUUUUUUUUUUUUUUUUUUUCAUAUUGAGACUAUUUUUCUAAUUAAGAAUAGGGGGUAGCCAUAAAGAGCUGUAUGUUGGAGGGGGAAACAUGGUGGGCGGGCAGUUUGGUUUUCUUUGUGUAUCCGCGUUUCUCUCACACUUCAUUUGUAGCAACUCAGGCCAGAUGUUUUCGUCUGAAAUUCUCUGGGCUUGUCAUUCCACCUGUAUCGUGCUGCAAACCAGGUGUUAUGCUAGUAGGCAUCUGCCCUCACCCCUCUGCCUGAGUUUUCUGUAGGCAGAUGUUAACCUGAGAAAACAAGUGCCAUGUGGACACCAAGUAAGCAUUUUUGAUAAUGAAUUAGAGCACCAGUUUCUACUGAAUGGAGCAAAAACCUUCAGCCAUGGCCAGGCUGCAUCCCUUUGGUCCUGGAGUUUCAUCUACUUACUGCCAUCUUCCACGGUCUUUGCACUGUCCCGUGUCCCAUCCCCCUGGGAGGCAGAAGAGAUUGCCUCGGAGUGGCCUUAUUUUUCUCGCAACUUGUGAAAUGAUGUAGUGCUCUAUGUAAUAUGGCCGGGUUUCCAAGCUGUCAUCCAAUGGAAGUAGAAUCUUCUCUUUGAAUCAUAUGGUACAGGUGCCAAUAUGACUGCUGCUAUUUAGAGUCAGAGAGGUGGAAGUCACUGGGUCCCUUUCCCAGUGACAGAGCCCAUGAUGUCUAACACUACUGCACUUUGUCAGUGUGUGAGUGAUGGCGAAUACGCAGUGUUGUCUCUUUGAUUUGGUAAUUCCGUUCCUGACAGUAAUGAGGCCACUGCUCUAAAGUAGUUUAUACAGUUCUUCAGUUGUAUAAAUAGCACAGAGUAGUUUUUGAAAGGUUAAGAAAAAUAAGUGAAAAGACAUACACGAUAUAUGAAAUGGCUCCAAAUGAUAAUUGUUCAAACCUUUAUAAAAUGUGUUUUCGUACUCUUAUGCUGCCAGAGGUACUUCUUAAAACUCUUCUCGUCUUGGUUUUAUAAGCACACCACGGAGGUCUGACAGAUGUGCUUGCUUCUACUACAGAGCAAGAGAAUUUGCACUUUAGCUAUAUGUGAAGGAUAUUAUUUUAACAAAUUCCUGAUUCUAAUAAAGUUAUUUUAUUACAUGAA